AUUUUUUGAUAAUUGGCCUCGACCCUCCUCACCUACUCCUUCCUUAGCCAAAUCUACUGAGAAAAGACUUGGAGGGGGACUCUCCCUCCACCCCUCCGUGGGCAAACUCCUGACGGACUGUAAGACCUUGGCCGCCCUCUCGCCUGGCCUGGGUCCCUCGAAUGAAUGUACAUCCGCCAACUGCGCGCCCCCUCUCACCGCAGCCCCGCGCGGGGCCCCAGGAUCGCAGGACCGCGGCGGCCGCAGGGAGCCACCAUGUUCAGCCAGCAGCAGCAGCAGCAGCUCCAGCAACAGCAGCAGCAGCUCCAGCAGUUACAGCAGCAGCAGCUCCAGCAGCAGCAAUUGCAGCAGCAGCAGUUACUGCAGCUCCAGCAGCUGCUCCAGCAGUCCCCACCACAGGCCCCGUUGCCCAUGGCUGUCAGCCGGGGGCUCCCCCCGCAGCAGCCACAGCAGCCGCUUCUGAAUCUCCAGGGCACCAACUCAGCCUCCCUCCUCAACGGCUCCAUGCUGCAGAGAGCUUUGCUUUUACAGCAGUUGCAAGGACUGGACCAGUUUGCAAUGCCACCAGCCACGUAUGACACUGCCGGUCUCACCAUGCCCACAGCAACACUGGGUAACCUCCGAGGCUAUGGCAUGGCAUCCCCAGGCCUCGCAGCCCCCAGCCUCACACCCCCACAACUGGCCACUCCAAAUUUGCAACAGUUCUUUCCCCAGGCCACUCGCCAGUCCUUGCUGGGACCUCCUCCUGUUGGGGUCCCCAUGAACCCUUCCCAGUUCAACCUUUCAGGACGGAACCCCCAGAAACAGGCCCGGACCUCCUCCUCUACCACCCCCAAUCGAAAGGAUUCUUCUUCUCAGACAAUGCCUGUGGAAGACAAGUCAGACCCCCCAGAGGGGUCUGAGGAAGCCGCAGAGCCCCGGAUGGACACACCAGAAGACCAAGAUUUACCGCCCUGCCCAGAGGACAUCGCCAAGGAAAAACGCACUCCAGCACCUGAGCCUGAGCCUUGUGAGGCGUCCGAGCUGCCAGCAAAGAGAUUGAGGAGCUCAGAAGAGCCCACAGAGAAGGAACCUCCAGGGCAGUUACAGGUGAAGGCCCAGCCGCAGGCCCGGAUGACAGUACCGAAACAGACACAGACACCAGACCUGCUGCCUGAGGCCCUGGAAGCCCAAGUGCUGCCACGAUUCCAGCCACGGGUCCUGCAGGUCCAGGCCCAGGUGCAGUCACAGACUCAGCCGCGGAUACCAUCCACAGACACCCAGGUGCAGCCAAAGCUGCAGAAGCAGGCGCAAACACAGACCUCUCCAGAGCACUUAGUGCUGCAACAGAAGCAGGUGCAGCCACAGCUGCAGCAGGAGGCAGAGCCACAGAAGCAGGUGCAGCCACAGGUACAGCCACAGGCACAUUCACAGGGCCCAAGGCAGGUGCAGCUGCAGCAGGAGGCAGAGCCGCUGAAGCAGGUGCAGCCACAGGUGCAGCCCCAGGCACAUUCACAGCCCCCAAGGCAGGUGCAGCUGCAGCUGCAGAAGCAGGUCCAGACACAGACAUAUCCACAGGUCCACACACAGGCACAGCCAAGCGUCCAGCCACAGGAGCAUCCUCCAGCGCAGGUGUCAGUACAGCCACCAGAGCAGACCCAUGAGCAGCCUCACACCCAGCCGCAGGUGUCGUUGCUGGCUCCAGAGCAAACACCAGUUGUGGUUCAUGUCUGCGGGCUGGAGAUGCCACCUGAUGCAGUAGAAGCUGGUGGAGGCAUGGAAAAGACCUUGCCAGAGCCUGUGGGCACCCAAGUCAGCAUGGAAGAGAUUCAGAAUGAGUCGGCCUGUGGCCUAGAUGUGGGAGAAUGUGAAAACAGAGCGAGAGAGAUGCCAGGGGUAUGGGGCGCCGGGGGCUCCCUGAAGGUCACCAUUCUGCAGAGCAGUGACAGCCGGGCCUUUAGCACUGUACCCCUGACACCUGUCCCCCGCCCCAGUGACUCCGUCUCCUCCACCCCUGCGGCUACCAGCACUCCCUCUAAGCAGGCCCUCCAGUUCUUCUGCUACAUCUGCAAGGCCAGCUGCUCCAGCCAGCAGGAGUUCCAGGACCACAUGUCGGAGCCUCAGCACCAGCAGCGGCUAGGGGAGAUCCAGCACAUGAGCCAAGCCUGCCUCCUGUCCCUGCUGCCCGUGCCCCGGGACGUCCUGGAGACAGAGGAUGAGGAGCCUCCACCAAGGCGCUGGUGCAACACCUGCCAGCUCUACUACAUGGGGGACCUGAUCCAACACCGCAGGACACAGGACCACAAGCCACCCACACCACGAAGAGAUGUGUUUGCCCACGUUCCAGUGCAGGGGUGGAGCACAGCCCGGCUUGUUACAGAUAUGAUUGCCAAACAAUCCUUGCGACCCUUCUGCACCGUUUGCAACCGCUACUUCAAAACCCCUCGCAAGUUUGUGGAGCACGUGAAGUCCCAGGGGCAUAAGGACAAAGCCAAGGAGCUGAAGUCGCUUGAGAAAGAAAUUGCUGGCCAAGAUGAGGACCACUUCAUUACAGUGGACGCUGUGGGUUGCUUCGAGGGUGAUGAAGAAGAGGAAGAGGAUGAUGAGGAUGAAGAAGAGAUCGAGGUUGAGGAGGAACUCUGCAAGCAGGUGAGGUCCAGAGAUAUAUCCAGAGAGGAGUGGAAGGGCUCGGAGACCUACAGCCCCAAUACUGCAUAUGGUGUGGACUUCCUGGUGCCCGUGAUGGGCUAUAUCUGCCGCAUCUGCCACAAGUUCUAUCACAGCAACUCAGGGGCACAGCUCUCCCACUGCAAGUCCCUGGGCCACUUUGAGAACCUGCAGAAAUACAAGGCGGCCAAGAACCCCAGCCCCACCACCCGACCUGUGAGCCGCCGGUGCGCAAUCAACGCCCGGAACGCUUUGACAGCCCUGUUCACCUCCAGCGGCCGCCCACCCUCCCAGCCCAACACCCAGGACAAAACACCCAGCAAGGUGACGGCUCGACCCUCCCAGCCCCCACUACCUCGGCGCUCAACCCGCCUCAAAACCUGAUAGAGGGACCUCCCUGUCCCUGGCCUGCCUGGGUCCAGAUCUGCUAAUGCUUUUUAGGAGUCUGCCUGGAAACUUUGACAUGGUUCAUGUUUUUACUCAAAAUCCAAUAAAACAAGGUAGUUUGGCUGUGCA